CCUCUCUCAUGACCCCGCUCCGGGAUUAUGGCCGGGACUGGGCUGCUGGCGCUGCGGACGCUGCCAGGGCCCAGCUGGGUGCGAGGCUCGGGCCCUUCCGUGCUGAGCCGCCUGCAGGACGCGGCCGUGGUGCGGCCUGGCUUCCUGAGCACGGCAGAGGAGGAGACGCUGAGCCGAGAACUGGAGCCCGAGCUGCGCCGCCGCCGCUACGAAUACGAUCACUGGGACGCGGCCAUCCACGGCUUCCGAGAGACAGAGAAGUCGCGCUGGUCAGAAGCCAGCCGGGCCAUCCUGCAGCGCGUGCAGGCGGCCGCCUUUGGCCCCGGCCAGACCCUGCUCUCCUCCGUGCACGUGCUGGACCUGGAAGCCCGCGGCUACAUCAAGCCCCACGUGGACAGCAUCAAGUUCUGCGGGGCCACCAUCGCCGGCCUGUCUCUCCUGUCUCCCAGCGUUAUGCGGCUGGUGCACACCCAGGAGCCGGGGGAGUGGCUGGAACUCUUGCUGGAGCCGGGCUCCCUCUACAUCCUUAGGGGCUCAGCCCGUUAUGACUUCUCCCAUGAGAUCCUUCGGGAUGAAGAGUCCUUCUUUGGGGAACGCCGGAUUCCCCGGGGCCGGCGCAUCUCCGUGAUCUGCCGCUCCCUCCCUGAGGGCAUGGGGCCAGGGGAGUCUGGACAGCCGCCCCCAGCCUGCUGACCCCCAGCUUUCUACAGACACCAGAUUUGUGAAUAAAGUUGGGGAAUGGACAGCCUAACUGGGACAUUGCAGUGGCUGCUUGCUGGGGCCGGGAUUUGCAGGGGAACCCAGGAUGGCACUGGCCCAUAGGGAGCUCCAGGUGUGGCUGGCUGGACACAUGGUCAAAGUCACAAGGCCGGGAGAGUGGUGUCCUUUAUUGCACUCACUGCUGGUCGCCCCAGCCCACUCCCCUCCUCGUUGUCUCUGCAUCCAGGUCUCCAAUAAAUAAGUCAGCCGA